CGGAGCCGCGCGAAGGGCGCCCCUCGACCCGGAGGCACAGGAGCGUUUAGAGAGGAAAGAAAGAAAAAGCCACCGCUGGCUCGAAUUUCUGGAAGCCGGAGCCGGGUUUUUUGCCCUAAACACCGAGGCAGAACCCCUCUUAGCGCUGCCCCGGCCUCUCUGUUACCCAUUUUCGGUUUGCUUUUGGAAGAACCGGUUCCUCAGCCCCCCGUCGCCGCAGUUGUGACACAAGUGCAGGGGUGUUGGAACCCUUUGAAGAAGUGUGUAGCUAAUAGCCCAUACAUAAUUCAGAAGAAGUCUUCAAUGGAAGACCCCCGGGGGAUAAAUGGACAGUCUGUCAAGUGGGAUCAUGGAUUCAAAUGUUCUUUGAAAAUGAAAAGUGCAACAUAACUCUAAUUCACUUUUUAUUGGAAACAUCUCCAGAAAAAUGAAUAAACGACCAUGAAUAAAAAAUUAUCUGGCCACCUGCAAGUCUACAAUACAAUUUUAAAAAUGUGACCAUCACACCUGCAUCAGCACCUUGAAUAACUCUAGUUUAUGUGGUUGCAAGUAAUGGAACUUACCAUGAGCUGGCAUAAGAAAACAAAAGGAAAGUCUUAAGAAAGAGGGCAUCUGGGGAAUUCAGGUGCAAACAUCUCAAGCCAGUUCAGAUGUUGCUGUUUCCUCAAGUUGCAGGUCUAUGGAAAUGCAGGAUCUAACCAGCCCGCAUAGCCGUCUGAGUGGUAGUAGUGAAUCCCCCAGUGGCCCCAAACUCGGUAACUCUCAUAUAAAUAGUAAUUCCAUGACUCCCAAUGGCACCGAAGUUAAAACAGAGCCAAUGAGCAGCAGUGAAACAGCUUCAACGACAGCCGACGGGUCUUUAAACAAUUUCUCAGGUUCAGCAAUUGGGAGCAGUAGUUUCAGCCCACGACCAACUCACCAGUUCUCUCCACCACAGAUUUACCCUUCCAACAGACCAUACCCACAUAUUCUCCCUACCCCUUCCUCACAAACUAUGGCUGCAUAUGGGCAAACACAGUUUACCACAGGAAUGCAACAAGCUACAGCCUAUGCCACGUACCCACAGCCAGGACAGCCGUACGGCAUUUCCUCAUAUGGUGCAUUGUGGGCAGGCAUCAAGACUGAAGGUGGAUUGUCACAGUCUCAGUCACCUGGACAGACAGGAUUUCUCAGCUAUGGCACAAGCUUCAGUACCCCUCAACCUGGACAGGCACCAUACAGCUACCAGAUGCAAGGUAGCAGUUUUACAACAUCAUCAGGAAUAUAUACAGGAAAUAAUUCACUCACAAAUUCCUCUGGAUUUAAUAGUUCACAGCAGGACUAUCCGUCUUAUCCCAGUUUUGGCCAGGGUCAGUACGCACAGUAUUAUAACAGCUCACCGUAUCCAGCACAUUAUAUGACCAGCAGCAACACCAGCCCAACGACACCAUCCACCAAUGCCACUUACCAGCUUCAAGAACCGCCAUCUGGCAUCACCAGCCAAGCAGUUACAGAUCCCACAGCAGAGUACAGCACAAUCCACAGCCCAUCAACACCCAUUAAAGAUUCAGAUUCUGAUCGAUUGCGUCGAGGUUCAGAUGGGAAAUCACGUGGACGGGGCCGAAGAAACAAUAAUCCUUCACCUCCCCCAGAUUCUGAUCUUGAGAGAGUGUUCAUCUGGGACUUGGAUGAGACAAUCAUUGUUUUCCACUCCUUGCUUACUGGGUCCUACGCCAACAGAUAUGGGAGGGAUCCACCCACUUCAGUUUCCCUUGGACUGCGAAUGGAAGAAAUGAUUUUCAACUUGGCAGACACACAUUUAUUUUUUAAUGACUUAGAAGAAUGUGACCAAGUCCAUAUAGAUGAUGUUUCUUCAGAUGAUAACGGACAGGACCUAAGCACAUAUAACUUUGGAACAGAUGGCUUUCCUGCUGCAGCAACCAGUGCUAACUUAUGUUUGGCAACUGGUGUACGGGGCGGUGUGGACUGGAUGAGAAAGUUGGCCUUCCGCUACAGACGGGUAAAAGAGAUCUACAACACCUACAAAAAUAAUGUUGGAGGUCUGCUUGGUCCAGCUAAGAGGGAAGCCUGGCUGCAGUUGAGGGCCGAAAUUGAAGCCCUGACCGACUCCUGGUUGACACUGGCCCUGAAAGCACUCUCGCUCAUUCACUCCCGGACAAACUGUGUGAAUAUUUUAGUAACAACUACUCAGCUCAUCCCAGCAUUGGCGAAAGUCCUGCUGUAUGGGUUAGGAAUUGUAUUUCCAAUAGAAAAUAUUUACAGUGCAACUAAAAUAGGAAAAGAAAGCUGUUUUGAGAGAAUAAUUCAAAGGUUUGGAAGAAAAGUGGUGUAUGUUGUUAUAGGAGAUGGUGUAGAAGAAGAACAAGGAGCAAAAAAGCACGCGAUGCCCUUCUGGAGGAUCUCCAGCCACUCGGACCUCAUGGCCCUGCACCAUGCCUUGGAACUGGAGUACCUGUAACAGCGCUCGGCACUUUGACAGCGCACAGCUGCUCUGUGACCAGGGACAGAUCCAGCAGGCCCCAGUCUCGCAUCAGCGCCGGCCUCCAGAACUUAGCAAUUUCCGCCUGGUGAUGCGCAGUUGCUGUCAGUCUUGACCUCUGCCUUUGUGGUGAAUGGAGGACCACGUCUAUUUCAUCAGAACAGCUGUUGACUCUAGUACUGUGAAUCCAGUGAAAAUAAGCCAUGAGAAUGUUUUAGCACAGCGUUAUGUGUCUGCCACAUUAACUACACGGUUCAAACCUGUGAAGAAAGGACCUGCAAACGCUUCAGUUGUUAGCAUUUUCAAUGUGAUAUAAACAGCUUCUCCAAUACAGCAAACCUAAUUGCACAACAGAGACUGAAAUGUGUUUCCUGAAUACCAGUGGAGGAAUUUUCUUGUAAAGAAGGUUUACUUUUUGGUGUCUCAUACCCAGGGUAAUCUGUACAUCUCUACUUAUUUAUGAACAGACUUUUUUUAAAAAGAUAAAAAAACAGCUUUAUUGAGGUAUAAUUCACCCACCAGACUUUUUUAAACAUCAAAUAAUUGAAGAGACAAUAGCAUUAGAAAUAAGUGAUUAAAGGCCUCUGCCUCACAACAUGGCAAGUACAGUACUUUGAAUUUUAGCACAUUGCAUAGUAGUUUUAAGUAUGUCUAAUUUAAACGUAUAAUAUGUACAUCACUGAGACAAUCAUGUACAGAAAGAAUUUUUGGUGUAAAUUUGUAAUAAUGGAUAAUUCUUUUACAUAUUGUUUAGGGAAAUGAUAUUGAAAGGUAGCAAUGCCUGGAUAGUGAAGCAUGAGGCAGCACGUGCACAAAUUCAUGUGCCGUGCCUUAUCUGAGUUUUCGGUAUAAAUAUGUAGAUAAUGGAUUUUUUUUUUUUAGAUAAUGUUGUCAAGACCAAAAGCAUGGAUGUCAAGUGUCAGUAAGGAUUUUGUUUUCUAAAAUUUUUUCCUGCAUCAGUUCUUCUGAGGGCCUUGAUGAAAUAACACAGCAGUUUCUUAAACAAUUUGAAACAAAAUGAGCUCUCCUACCACCUCACUUUUUCAUUUCCACACUAAUGUAUUAUAUGUAACUACUUGGAAAAAAUAAUUAUUCAAAUGCUUCUUCCCACAAAGAAUAUAGAUGAUAGUAGAUAUAUUUUAUUAAUAAAAUGGUUCAUGAAUCGGAGACUAACAAAGUUUUCAUGUGCUCAGAAUUAUUAAUUAUCGUGUCUGCAUUUUCUUUCGAUAAAGGAAGACACACGAUGCUAAUCCGGAAAUCAGCAAACUUUGCAUUACUCCCUAUGUGCGUAUUUUCUCUUUCUUCCUGUCACCCUGAGGAAGGUUCAUUGCCAUUGUCAUCACCAUGGAAACAACGUUCCUCUCCACCUGCAUUAUGUACUACAUGACAGGCAUCAAUCUGGGGAAAUAAUAAAAUUAUCACCUUUGUCAGACCAUAAGAGUUUCUCCAAAAGUGGUCAGUUUGGCUGGGCAAUAUUUUCUCUCAUCUAACAAACACAAUCCAUUGUCAUGAAAUUACCCUUAGGAUGAGUCUUCUUUAAUCAAUCAUAUAUUGGGCGGGAAAAACACCAGCUUUGACCCGAAGUAGUUGAAGAGCUACUUCAUUCUUUUCUGAAGUUGUGUGUUGCUGCUAGAAAUAGUCAUUUGUGAAUUAUCCAAAUUGUUUAAAUUCACAAUUGAAUUAGUUUUUUCUUCCUUUUUGCUUGAAGCAAACAGUUGACAAUUUUUAACCUUUUCAUUUUAUGUUUUUGUACUCUGCAGACUGAAAAGACAAAGUUUAUCUUGGCCUUACUGUAUAAAGGUGUGCUGUGUCCACCGUUGUGUACAGAAUUUUUCUUCAUUAAUUUUGUGUUUAAGUUAAUAAAAUUUAUUUGUGAUGUACUGUAA